AGCGUCGCCGCGAGGCCACCCGGAAGACCAAGCCGGGUAGGCGCUGUCUCCGUCGCCUCCAACCCCCCCGGUCCGACCAGGGAAGGUGGGAUGCUCUGAUGGCCGGGCCUGCGGCGCUGAGCGCGGCGGCGGCGGCUGCUCUGGCGGCCGCCCUGCUCCUGCUGCGUCGUGAGGACCCGGGGCCGGGGGCUGGCCCCAGGUAACCCCUCCGCGUAUGGGACCGAGCUGGGCCAGGUCUCCUGGCCGGGCCGGGGAUACCGUGGGGUAUGCCCAGUGAUGCCAGCAGCUUGUGGCACCUGGGCGCACCCUCCAGCUCGGGCCCCUUCCGAUGGGUCUGCUGGCUCAGGUGCGGGCGAUGGCCGGGGAGCCGCGCCCCGCACGUGACUCAGCACUUUCCCCAGAGCCCGGACUGCGGAGAACAAUAUCCUCCUCCCUAACAGAUAAACAGCCCUUGUUCCUCGGGAUAAGGACUGGCAGUCCCCUGACACCCUAAGACCGGCAUCUGUCGAUGUUAUUUCCCCAGCAUGGCCGAAACAGAAGCCCUGUCGAAGCUUCGGGAAGACUUCAGGAUGCAGAAUAAAUCCGUCUUUAUUUUGGGCGCCAGCGGAGAAACCGGCAGAGUGCUCUUAAAGGAAAUCCUGGAGCAGGGCCUGUUUUCCAAAGUCACGCUCAUUGGCCGGAGGAAGCUCACCUUCGACGAGGAAGCUUAUAAAAAUGUGAAUCAAGAAGUGGUGGACUUUGAAAAGUUGGAUGACUACGCCUCUGCCUUUCAAGGUCAUGAUGUUGGAUUCUGUUGCCUGGGUACCACCAGAGGGAAAGCUGGGGCGGAGGGAUUUGUUCGUGUUGACCGAGAUUAUGUGCUGAAGUCUGCAGAGCUGGCAAAAGCUGGAGGGUGCAAACAUUUCAACUUGCUAUCCUCUAAAGGAGCUGAUAAAUCAAGCAAUUUUUUAUAUCUACAAGUUAAGGGAGAAGUAGAAGCCAAGGUUGAAGAAUUAAAAUUUGAUCGUUACUCUGUAUUUAGGCCUGGAGUUCUGUUAUGUGAUAGGCAAGAAUCUCGCCCAGGUGAAUGGCUGGUUAGAAAGUUCUUUGGCUCCUUACCAGACUCUUGGGCCAGUGGGCAUUCUGUGCCUGUGGUGACCGUGGUUAGAGCAAUGCUGAACAAUGUGGUGAGACCAAGAGACAAGCAGAUGGAACUGCUGGAGAACAAGGCCAUCCAUGACCUGGGGAAAGCGCAUGGCUCUCUCAAGCCAUGACCACAUUGGAGAAAUGGUUUUUAUUGUCAACCUUAACACCCAUCACCAAAUCGGUAAUUUCAGGGUCUAAAAAAAGUCAGCAUGUUUUAACUUUGUUGUUUUACUAUCCUCAGGCAUCCAUUCCAAUCAAGAAAUGAUGGUGCUCUGCAUCAGUGGUUCAGAGCCUGGUUAUACAUAUAGAUCACUCAGGGAGCUUUGGAAAAAUAAAGAUUUGUCAGCCCUAUCUCAAACUUGAAUCAAAAUUUCUGGGGUGUGGGCACAAUAAUCUGUAAUUUUCUUUGUUUAUACUUCCCCUGAUGCCACUGGUUCCGAUGCCACUGGCUGGGGGGCCUGCUUUGAAAUGCUUGUCUGCAGAGUCACAGCAGCCAUGAAAACCUUAUGACCGUGCAAAUGAGCUCUGCUCUAAAAUUGUUGACAUUCAUGUCUCUGAGUUACAAAAGUGCUAAUUCACUACAUGUAAUUGUGUAAGUAAACAUUGUGCCUUUACUACUUCUUUAUGUAAUAGAAGUUAUAUACCUAAGCUUAUAUAAUACAUGGGGAGGAUUAAAUAAAGGAAUAAAGAUGAAUGGACAACUCC